AUCUUGUUCCCAGGGGCAGUUGGCGGAAGAGAUCGAGCUCCCUGGCUGCCGGCUCGCCUUCUGCGUGGAGUUCUCGCGGUCUGGGUUUCGCUGUCUGCUCUUGGCCCGGGGUCAUUUUGUCGGCGUCGGGUGCCCUCUCUUGCCCAGCUGGGGCACAGCGAGGCGGCCCCUUCUCCCGACGACGUUCGAUGGAGUAGGGUCCCAGACCGUUGUCCCGAAGAGCGAGAUCGAGCUUGGCCCCCUCCCCCCCCUCCUUCCCUCCCUCCUUCCUUCCGCCGCAACAUGGCUAACAACAGCCCCGCGCUGACAGGCAACUCGCAGCCGCAGCACCAGGCGGCUGCAGCUGCGGCUCAGCAACAGCAGCAGUGCGGCGGCGGCGGCGCUACCAAGCCGGCGGUCUCCGGCAAGCAGGGCAAUGUGCUCCCGCUCUGGGGCAACGAGAAGACCAUGAACCUCAACCCCAUGAUCCUGACCAACAUCCUGUCGUCGCCUUACUUCAAAGUACAGCUCUACGAGCUCAAGACCUACCACGAGGUGGUGGACGAGAUCUACUUUAAGGAUUGACUCAGUCUUGCAGCGAGGCUCGGAGCAGCCCAGGGUCGCAGGUAGAGGUCACGCACGUUGAACCAUGGGAGAAAGGAAGCAGGAAAACAGCGGGCCAGACAGGGAUGUGCGGAGGGGUAAGUAGAAGUUCGAGGUGUUGGAACAGGAGGAAUUGUUUCUACAGCAUUUUGCCUGUUAUACAAAUUAUUUACCCUGAAGUUAACUCGAAAGCAAGUGAUGGGUCUUAUAACACACACAGACUCUCCAUAUAUUAGAGCGCUUGGAUUUAUGUAUAUAAGAUAUACACAGCCCCCUACAGAUCUGUGGGACUGGUUUGAAUCCUUCCUUGAUGAUGAAGAGGUUUGGGACUGACAAUAGCUGACUAACAUGUCCUGAGCUGUGAGAGGGCAUAGCAAGAAGGCCUUCAUGCGGACCUAGAUGUGAAGGCUGGUGGAGGCUGUGUAAUGACCAUUGGAGAAAUGCUACGAUCUUUUCUCACAAAACUGGAGUGGUUUUCUACCUUGUUUCCAAGAAUUCCAGUUCCAGUUCAAAAGAAUAUUGAUCAACAGAUUAAAACCCGACCUAGAAAAAUCAAGAAAGAUGGGAAGGAAGGUGCUGAGGAAAUAGACAGACAUGUUGAACGCAGACGUUCAAGGUCUCCAAGGAGAUCUCUGAGUCCACGGAGGUCCCCAAGAAGGUCAAGAAGUAGAAGUCAUCAUCGGGAGGGCCAUGGGUCUUCUAGUUUUGACAGAGAAUUAGAAAGAGAGAAAGAACGCCAGCGACUAGAGCGUGAAGCCAAAGAAAGGGAGAAAGAACGGCGAAGAUCCCGAAGUAUUGACCGGGGGUUAGAACGCAGGCGCAGCAGAAGUAGGGAAAGGCAUAGAAGUCGCAGUCGAAGUCGUGAUAGGAAAGGGGAUAGAAGGGACAGGGAUCGAGAAAGAGAGAAAGAAAAUGAGAGAGGUAGAAGACGAGAUCGUGACUAUGAUAAGGAAAGAGGAAAUGAACGAGAAAAAGAGAGAGAGCGAUCAAGAGAAAGGUCCAAGGAACAGAGAAGUAGGGGAGAGGUAGAAGAGAAGAAACAUAAAGAAGACAAAGAUGAUAGGCGGCACAGAGAUGACAAAAGAGAUUCCAAGAAAGAGAAAAAACACAGUAGAAGCAGAAGCAGAGAAAGGAAACACAGAAGUAGGAGUCGAAGUAGAAAUGCAGGGAAACGAAGUAGAAGUAGAAGCAAAGAGAAAUCAAGUAAACAUAAAAAUGAAAGUAAAGAAAAAUCAAAUAAACGAAGUCGAAGUGGCAGUCAAGGAAGAACUGACAGUGUUGAAAAAUCAAAAAAACGGGAACAUAGUCCCAGCAAAGAAAAAUCUAGAAAGCGUAGUAGAAGCAAAGAACGUUCCCACAAACGAGAUCACAGUGAUAGUAAGGACCAGUCAGACAAACAUGAUCGUCGAAGGAGCCAAAGUAUAGAACAAGAGAGCCAAGAAAAACAGCAUAAAAACAAAGAUGAGACUGUGUGAAAAUAUUUUGUAAAAGUGGAUCACAUUGAAUCCUAUAAAUGAUUAAAUCUGCUUUUUUCCCCCACGUUGAGAUUGUGCAGUAGUUCGCACUCCUCAAGCUCUCCCUGUAGGCUGCAUUUUCAUUUCCUCUUUCGUGUAGGGAAGUGCCUUUGUAAUUCCAUUUAUUGCAUUGGUGUUUUCACCCAAUUGUUAAGUUUGAUACAUGAUGCACAGAUUGUUCUUGCAUUUUUAUUGUUUGUUUUUGAAAUGUACAGUCUGUACAUAUGUCCUGAAAAUGUUUUAAUUCCUUUGGCAUGGUUGCCAUGUUGGUUAAAUUUGUAUAAGGCAAUAAACUGCCACUAAUCUAUUUUUGUUUUGUAGGUGUGGGAUUAUGGUUUGUGUACUGAAGUUAGCAUGGCUGUGCUUUUCGUAAUAGAAUGCUAAAGACUUUGAGAAUGGAUCUUGGAUGUCUAUUAUAGGAGAAGUAUGUGCUGCCAAUGUACAAGAAGGCAGCAUUGUAGGAUUAACAUUCUUGUCUACUGUAUAUUAUCUUGGAAGGCUCUUGUUAAUAUGUUACACUUAAUAUUCUCCACAGUUACCUUUAGAGAGAAUUUAUGAGAAGUUAGUUUCUGAUGCAGAGGUUUUUAGGCUGUGAUUUCAUCAAAAGUCCUUUUAGCAUUCUACCUCAAAGGGACACUUAGUAUGCCUAAAAUUUAUUCACUUAGUUUUCCUUUUUUAUUUGAAAAAAUACAUGACAUGUAAUCUUUUUUUCUUGAAUUCUUUCUCAGAUUUUAAAGUACUAUAUUAAAGAAAAAAAUUAAUGUCUAAAGCCUAGCAUUCUUGCAGAACCCUAUACUAACAUGUAAUGGGGAGAGGGUGGGGCAGAUGAGUAGAGAAACAGAUUCAAGCCUCAAGCUUCCAAAGCAUUUUUAUAAAUGGAAAAUCCUUAAAUUAUGAAACAGCUUGAUAUAGUGUCCUUUUUUUAAAAUUCAGAACUUUUUUUAUUGAUAAUGGAGAUUGCUGUUUGAGUUUUUAAACUUAAUCUAGAACAGAGGAGUAUUAAAAGUAAUGCUGUGCUGCAUUAUUUAAGACUAUCAGCAAAUUAUUUGAUAGAUUGUUCUUACAACUUGUAUUCUGAUUACAGAACCAUCAUGAGUGUGGAAUAAAUACUGGAUUAAAUCCUUUAUCCUGGGUCUUGGCUUUUCCCCCAUUUGUUAAAUUUUUUUAGCAUAUUUAUAUUGUGGAAAUUGAUGAAACGUCAGUAGAGUCACACUUUGUGUACAGGGAUGUCUUAGUGCCCAGAUGACAAGUGAAUUUUGGAGAAAUGCAUAGACUGGGAUUGGGCAUGUGGUAAUCAAUAAUCUUUAUUAGAAUACUUGAUAAUGGCAGUUCCCUUUGUCAGUGGUUGUUACAUGUGUCAUUUGAUUACUUUGUUCCAUGUCAAAGACGUUUAUUGGGAUACCUUUUACUUGGACAAUAUGUUAGCAUUUUUUAAAAUUUGGACUUGAAAUUCUUUAAGAUAAUUCACCCAAUUCUUUUUAGAAAAGAAAAUAGAGGCCCAAAGUAAUGAUGUCAGUGCUAGGGCUAAAACUCAGUAUUCUGACAGUGUAGUGAACCUGGCACGCACAUUGAGGUUUGUUUUAUCUCACUGGUUAUACUGGCCAACUAAUGCGCACUCAGAAGCCACCUUGCAAAAAUGUUAAAUGGAGCAAACGAGUACACUUGCAAGAGUCCUCCAUAUGUGGGCUUAACAUAUGUACCACUCCAUUUUAGAAAAAUCUCAUUAAAUGAAUUCUUCUAAAAAUGAUAUGCUUUUUUCUUUUUUAAGAAAAUUCCUUUGUCUUUUAAAUUGAGCAUCAAGUGAAUUAGUGCUAUAGACACCCAGAAGUUAGAAAAACCUAUUGUAUAAUAUGAAAGCCACUAAAUUUGUCUUGUGUUGAAAAUCUACUUUUAGCAUACCUAAAUUAUGGAGCUACUACUUUGGAUAUGGUUCCAUGUGAAAUGUUUUAUCUGACUAUUUUAAGUAAAAUGUGGAAAGAAUUUAAAUUACUUCACAUGGAGGUGAAAGAACUAUCACCUCGAUUGACAGUUCGAUGAUCGUCACUACAUUUGAUUUCUUGUGGGUUUUUAGUUUGUUUUUGUUUUGAGACGGGCCUGGCUCUGUCACCCAGACUGGAGUGCAGUGGUGCAAUCUCUGCUCACUGCAGCCUCCACUUCCCUGGCUCAAGUGAUCCUCCGAACUUGGCCUCCUAAGUAGCUGGGACCACAGGUGCAUGCUAGCACACCCGGCUAAUUUGUAUUUUUGGUAGGGUUGGGAUUUCGCCAUGUUGCCCAGGCUGGUCUUGAACUCCUGGCCUCAAGUGAUCCACCCACCUCAGCCUCCCAAAGCGCUGUGAUUACAGGUGUGAGCCACCACUCCAGUCCCUUCUUACGAUUUUUAAAUAUGUUUGCUUUUGAGGAAAAUUAUGGUAGGUGUGAGAACAUGUAAAUUGUGCUAGUUAUUGCUAUAUAUAUGCAUGAUUUAUUUGGAGAGUGGCUUCCUAAGAAACUGGGAAAACAAGUGGCUAUGAAAGACAUCUCACAUUUCUUGAAACAUGAGAACAUUUGGACACGAACAUCACACGCCGGGGCCUGUUGUGGGGUGGGGGACUAGGGGAGGGAUAAUAUUAGGAGAAAUACCUAAUGUAGAUGACAGGUUGAUGGGUGCAGCUCACCACCAAGGUACAUGUAUAUCUAGGUAACAAACCGGCACGUUCUGCACAUGUAUCUGAACUUAAAGUAUAAUUUAAAAAAAUUUUUAAUACAGCUUAAUAAGCAUCCUCCAUCCAGUUUUUGUACUUACUGGAAUGAUUUCACCUUUCCAUGUAUUAAAAUCUUUUGCCUGUUUUUAAUGUUCAAUUUGCAAUUAAAUUCUAUACAUGGGCGAGUA